GUUUUCGCCUCUCAGUUGCAGCAGAGAAGCCCCUGGCACCCGACUCUAUCCACCACCAGGAAGCCUCCCAAAAGAGCUCUCGCCCUGUGGACGACUCGGAAUCCCUGGAAAAGCCGGGAGGGAGUCGGAGGCGCCAGCCCACUGGGGAGGUGGCGCUGGGCGCGCGGGAUGCGCGGGGAGCCUUCUCUGCAGGAGCCGCACAGUGCACUGCUGCGCGCUGGGCAGUGCGGGGAAGCGCCGCGGGAAGGAGCGGCUCCGAGCAACAGGUGCAGCACGCAGCCCCUCCGGGAGCCAGGGAAAACCGCCGGCGAAGAUCUGGAGCGGUAAGGCGGAGAGAAGGGUCUUUCCACCUGCGCGGCUGCAGCCGGCGGAUCCCUCUUCCCAGGCUCCGUGGUCGCGCAGCGGGCGGAGGCGCCCGGGAAGGGGACCCCAGUGCUCUCGAGAUCACCGUCCCUUCCCGAGAAGGUCCAGCUCCGGGCUCCCGAACCCACCCUCUCUCAGAAGGUCCCGGCGCAAAGACGGUGCCACCAGGCACGGCCACCGGAUCCCCGCUCCCGCUGGCUCGCGCCUCGGGGGAAGCUCAGACUCCUAAACUCGCACUCUCCGUGCUUUGCGCCGGGACCCCUGGCCACCCCCGGCGCCUACUAUCCCGCCCUCCCUCCCCGCGCGCCCCGCCGCUCGCCGGGACAGCCCCGCGGGCCAUGGAGCUGGCGGUCGGGAACCUCAGCGAGGGCAACGCGAGCUGGCCGGAGCCCCCCGCCCCGGAGCCCGGGCCGCUGUUCGGCAUCGGCGUGGAGAACUUCGUCACGCUGGUGGUGUUCGGCCUGAUCUUCGCGCUGGGUGUGCUGGGCAACAGCCUAGUGAUCACCGUGCUGGCGCGCAGCAAGCCGGGCAAGCCGCGGAGCACCACCAACCUGUUCAUCCUCAACCUGAGCAUCGCCGACCUGGCCUACCUGCUCUUCUGCAUCCCCUUCCAGGCCACCGUGUACGCGCUGCCCACCUGGGUGCUGGGCGCCUUCAUCUGCAAGUUCAUCCACUACUUCUUCACCGUGUCCAUGCUGGUGAGCAUCUUCACCCUGGCCGCGAUGUCCGUGGACCGCUACGUGGCCAUCGUGCACUCGCGGCGCUCCUCCUCCCUCAGGGUGUCCCGCAACGCGCUGCUGGGCGUGGGCUGCAUCUGGGCGCUGUCCAUUGCCAUGGCCUCGCCCGUGGCCUACCACCAGGGCCUCUUCCACCCGCGCGCCAGCAACCAGACCUUCUGCUGGGAGCAGUGGCCCGACCCUCGCCACAAGAAGGCCUACGUGGUGUGCACCUUCGUCUUCGGCUACCUGCUGCCGCUCCUGCUCAUCUGCUUCUGCUAUGCCAAGGUCCUUAAUCACUUGCAUAAAAAGUUGAAGAACAUGUCAAAGAAGUCUGAAGCAUCCAAGAAAAAGACUGCACAGACAGUUCUGGUGGUGGUUGUGGUGUUUGGAAUCUCCUGGCUGCCGCACCACAUCAUCCAUCUCUGGGCUGAGUUUGGAGUUUUCCCGCUGACGCCGGCUUCCUUCCUCUUCAGAAUCACCGCCCACUGCCUGGCGUACAGCAAUUCCUCCGUGAAUCCUAUCAUUUAUGCAUUUCUCUCUGAAAAUUUCAGGAAGGCCUAUAAACAAGUGUUCAAGUGUCACAUUCGCAAAGAUUCACACCUGAGUGAUACUAAAGAAAGUAAAAGUCGAAUAGACACCCCACCAUCAACCAAUUGUACUCAUGUGUGAUAAAAGAUAGAGUAUCCUUAUGGUUGAGUUUCCAUAUAAGUGGACCAGACACAGAAACAAACAGAAUGAGCUAGUAAGCGAUGCUGCAACUUGUUAUCUUAACAAGAAUUCAAGUCGUUUUAAUUAAAUCCCACGUGUGUUAAAAAGUACUUUGAUCCAUUUAGGAAAUUCCUAGGUCUAGUGAGAAUUAUUUUUCAAUUUUAUUUUAGUUCUAAAUUAUGUUUCAGAAACAAAAGACAAUGCUGUACAGUUUUAUUCCUCUUCAGACAUGAAAGGGAACAUAUAUAUUCCAUAUAUAUGUUCAACUCUUCAUAGAUUGUGAACUGGCCCAUCAAUAUGGUCAGGAAUAUUUGCAGUCUACAUUUUAAAGCCAAUUUAUUUAGAAAAAAAAAUUUGAGCUUUAAUUCUUUAAUUUUAAGAGAAGUAAUAUUGUGAACUAUGUAUUUUAAAAUAUGAUCAUGGACACACAAUGAUGAAUUUUUUGGCCAUUUACAUAGACAUAUCUAUUAAGUGGAAAGAAGGCUUUCUGAAGUCUGUUUGCACAGGUGGCAUUUGCUUCCAAUUGUAGCUAGCGCACAGAGCUUUGGAAGCCUGUCAUUAUGAGAUACAGUCGGUUUACCUCAGGAGUCAAUUCAGUGUUGUACUGGUGACCUGGGAUGCAGUAGUAGGCACUGUUGAUUCAAAUUUAUCCUGUGAAACUGGCUUUAUAGAGUUAACAAAACAGAGUCAGAGACCACUGUCUUAACAGUGGAAGAUGCAAAUAAGUUUUUGAGAAUAAAACUGGAUUUUGAAAUUUUACAUUAGUACUUGACAAAAGUUUUCAUUUUGCCUUGAAUGGAACCUACUAAAAAGAGAGAUGAAAAAAAAUCAGCGAGGUUGAUGUAGAUAAUAAUUUCUAUGGGACCAAAGACUAGACAGAAUUCAGUAAGUCACAUGAAGUAAUGGUCAUGCCUGUACAUAAAGCAUAUUUCAUGUUUGAUUUAGAUGACAUUCAAAAAAAAUCAUGGGACUGAAUAUACCUGGGGUAUCCUAUCUUGUACAAAUGCAUGCUUUUUCAUUAAAUUUGUAAUGAUGUUUAAUGAACAUUUCCACCAAACAUUAUUUCCUCUAAAAAUGUUAAUUUGGGGUUAAAACCAUCACCAUUUGAAUUUCAAAUGUAGUUUUCAUGACAAUUUUAUAUUGAUGUGUGUUUACAAUGAGAAAAUGGCAUGAAAAUAUUAAAUUGUCUUGUAUCGGAAAAGUACUUUUCAGACUGUAAGACUUUGAUAUGUUUUAGGAGGCAACAAAAGCAAGAAGUUUUUUUUUUGUUUGUUUGUUAAAAAGGAUUUGGCCAAGCACAGUGGCUCAUGCCUGUAAUUCCAGCACUUUGGGAGGUCCAGCUGUGUGGAAUGUACUUGAGCUCAGGAGUUUGAGACCAGUGUGGGCAACAUGGCAAAACUCGGUCUCUACUAAAAAUACAAAAAUUAGCUGGGUGUGGUGGCGCACGCCUGUAGUUUCAGCUACUCUGGAGGCUGAUGUGGGGGAUCACCUGAGCCCGGGAGGUCCAGGAUGCAGUCAGUCAAGACUGCACCACUGCACUUCAGCCUGGAUGACAGAGUAAGACUCUGUCUAAAAUAUAUAUAUAUAUGUGUGUGUGUGUGUGUGUGUGUGUGUGUGUGUGUAAUGUACCUCUGUGCCAAAUCAGCACUCCACAUGAAACAUCAAAUUUUAGAUAAAAAUGCAAACUUGACAUAAGCCUUUGGCAUGCUAAUUUUUUUAGCUCAUUCACUUACUUUCACUAAUCAUAUUUCAGUGACUAGUGUUUACAUUUGCAAUGUUAUUAAUAACUCUCUGGAUAAAAGGAAAGAAAAACGUUAGAAAGAUUUUGAAGUGAUGUAUUAUGUUUGUUGACUAGAAGAAGAAAUUGUGUUUAUGUGUAAGUGAGGGUCUUAAAGAAUAUGUCCUUUGCAUCGAAUGUUUUUUGCACUUUAUUCAAAUAUAUAGGAGCAGAAAAAUUUUAUCCUGACGAUGAUACUUCCUGUGAUUUGUGGAACUUGAAGUUGCUGUUGCAAACUCCAGAACAACUUCUUUGGGUGUGAACUCACAAAACUGUGUAAAGAAGUGCCUUCUUGUUGUGUUUGAGUUUGCAUGAAUGGAAAUGAUUUCUUGCACCAUGGCUAUUUCUUUGUUUUCUCCUUCUGAUCUGUAAGCAUAUAAAUGGAAGUAUUUAAAAAAAUACUGUAGCUAAUGUUGCUAUUUUCUAGAGGCAUGCCGAAAAUGUGCUGUGCCUUUGGUCCUUCCCAGAUGCUACUGGCACGUCUGAAGCUUGAGGCAUGGUACAAAAAGUAAUAGCUUGCGCUUGAAACCCCCCCCCCCCCGCCACUUUGCUAAAUGUAAAUGCUAAUUGUUGCAUUUUACAGUUAGAUAGGAUAUACUUCCUGCAUAUUGUCAUUCUAAUCAAUUCCUCUUACUCAGAGUUUUGGCUGAGUCUACUUCUAAAACAAAUUUUGAUAGGGAUAAUGACAUCUUCUGCAAAGAUCUAAACCUCUACAAAAUUUUCUGAAUAAAGAGUUUCAGAAGAACUCGUAAACAGAAUGAAAUUAACCAGAGAAGUAUAGGAGUGUGUUGCGUUUGCCAAGCAUCUGCUUCCCAGCUAGAUUUCCCCCUAAUAUACAAUGACCAAUUCUGAAGCACCUUCUUUUCCGUCACUAAAUAAAGACAGCUUCCCAAGGACACACUUUUUCUCCCAGCAUCAGGUUGAGGGAGAAAUAUUGCUUAUACCUUUGAAGUCAGGCUGCUUGAAACUCACAUUUUCAGUUUACUUCAAAGAAAACUGAUGCUUUCUAAGCAGAUUUGGCUGUCUCAGUGCCCAAGGCAGCUGUUAUUUUCCUAGGCUUUUUGCUUUCACGUAAGGAGACAGGCUUUGGGAUAUUUAGUAGCUGAAAUGCUUGCUGUUUCACAUGCAUAAGCAACCAUUUCAGUGUCCUGCUGAUGAAUACAGUGAUGUGGAUGGAAACGUUUUCUUGUCCUAUAUCCUGGGGAUAGGAAACAGAUUCUCUGUGCUCUUCUGACCGGGUAUGUACUCAGCAACAUGGGGGACUGAGGCCAUUUUCUGAAUACUUUAGGUAAAUUACUUUUGCUUUUAACUAAAUUGUUUUAUUUUACACAUUGGGAGUAAAACCAUUUCCGCCCCAUCCCAAUCUCUUGUGCUUUUAUCUUUUUUAUCCUAACUCACUUCUAUCCAGAUUUCCUCUCGAUAAUAUUUACCACAGAUAAAUUCAUCUUUCAGCGCAGAUAUAACAAAUCAGAGUGGGGAGGAGAGAUGCUUAAGGAACUGCAUGAGUCAUGCAAGGCUCAGAACUUCUUGUGGCUCAACUCGAAAUCAUAUUGCAUUCCUGCAUUCUCCCAGAUGCUUUGAGGCAGUGCAGCGAUCAUUCUAAUAUGUUAACUGAGACCCAAGAUCUCAGCAGGAGAGGACAGCUUAUCCAAGCAUCCCUUUCCUUUUCAGUCAUGGCCAUGGCUAUCUGUAAACACCAAAAUGCUCAUGCUGAAGCAGCAUUACAUUGAGGAAAAUAACCUAUUGGGCAGCUUCAUCAUGUUCUUGCUUUAAAUGAUUUAUCAAAUACAUGUAUGUAAACUACAUAGUCACUAACUGCGAAAAUACAUCAAUGUGGCUACUUCCUCUGGAAAGUUACUGUCUAAAAUUUGUAAAUUUUAAUCUUCACUGUUGCACAUAUUUUCCAUGUCUUAAAUUUGUAAGUGGGUUUCUAUGAAAGGUAAUCGUAUUCUUCUUGACCAUUAAAAAUGUUGCAUGUAAGGCUAUUUCUCAAGUAGAUGUUAAUGACUUGUUUAAUUAUUGACUUACUUAUUUUAAAAGCUGUAUGUAGUAAGAACAAGUAGGUGGUUUAAAAUUCAGAUAGUUACAUGUUGGCCUGGAAAGAACAAAAUUAUGAAAUGGUAAUUAUAUCUGAUUUUAUUUAACCAUAUUUUAAUAUUUUCUCUUUUAGAAGUGGAAAAGUUGAGCCUGAGGAAGAAUUUAAAAUGCUUAAGACAUCUUUGAUGGGGGCUGUAUUUGCAUUAGGCAGAGGUGUCUAAGGAGAGUGUAUCGUGUAUUGUGAUGCAUUAGCAGGAUGUUUUGUUCAUCGACUUGUGAAAGUGCUGUGGAUAAUAGAUGGUGGUUUCUUUUCUUAGUGUGGCAGGUUCACUCACAUUCAUGUUUUUGACUUUAGCUGCCAUCCUGGGGUUCUGAGGGUAGCAUGUCUGUUUGACUGGGCAAGACCCUCACAUACCUUGGCAGGCCCUGGCUUUCGUUUCUCUGUGGUGCCUGGUGCUACUCACAGGGCUGACUCACGGGCAGAUGCUCCCCAUCCUUCCCCAUAGGCCCUGUUCCCGCAUCCGAUGAUUCUCAGGUUUUGUUCUAGGUGCAGAAAUAGUGGGAGAGGCCAUAAUCGUGAAUGAUGAAUAAGAAGGGAAGGUGGGGCCGGGCAUGUGACUUAUGCCUGUAAUCCCAGCACUUUGGGAGGCCGAGGCAGGUGGAUCACCUGAGGUCGGGAGUUCGAGACCAGCCUGACCAACAUGGAGAAAACCCGUCUCUACUAAAAAUACAAAAAUUAGCUGGGGGCACACAUGUGUGAUCCCAGCUACUCAGGAGGUUGAGGCAGGAGAAUUGCUUGAACCCGGGAGGUGGAGGUUGCAAUGAGCCUAGAUUGCACCAUUGCACUCCAGCCUGGGCAACAAGAGUGAAACUCUGUCUCAAAAAAAUAAAAAUUAAAAAAAAAAAAGAAGGUGGCCAGUGAGGGUUUUAUCUUUGUAUUCACUGGAAAUAACCUCAGCUGAAUUUUCUCUCUGAAUCUUUUCAAUGUUGGCUCCAUUUGCCAUACUCAGACAAUUGCUUGAAGAGCUGAACUGUUAGCUCAAGAUUUCGUUGGCACUGUUGGAUAGAAAGCCUCUCCUUUUCUGCUGGAGAAGAGAUUUCUCAGGCCAAGUUGUGUAGCUCCAAAUUCUCCGCAAUUAGAGAAGGCACAGUAAAGAAAAGAUCCCUUGCUGAUGGAAUGGACUGGAACUGAGCUCCACUGUUUAAAUUUUUGACUCUCAGGUAGUGGUGAUCGUUAUGGUAACCCAUGAACUCGGAUGAAUUUCGGGGCCUGCUGUGGGUUUUCUAUGGGACACCAUAUACCACAGUACUGUAUUUCAAAAUAUUGGAUAUUGAUUAUGAACACUGGAACUAUUUAUGUGUCAUCAUUCCAAAGACCAUUGUGAUCUAUGAAGCUCCUUUAUUUGCUGGCUAGAUUGUCCAAAAACAAGCUCACUUGUUUUUGGGCAAUCUAGCCAAGGUGUCACAUAAUGGAGAAAAAUGCAGAUGGUCCUGUGGCUGGUGUGAAUGAAGAAUGACCUGGGCCCAACAUAGAACUUUUCCAGUAUGGUGAGCAUCAAAGUAGGCAGACAUCCAAAAGCCAAGUGAAGGGCAGAUAGAUCCCCAGGUGCCACCCAGGCUCUGCAGGCAAAGCUCUCAGGGCCCCAUUUGUGUUUGUGUGGCCUGCACUGUGUAAGUGUCGUUCCCCUAGGACUUCUGCAAUGGGAUACCAAAGAUGACGUGUAAGGCCUUCAGUAUAUAAUGGACUUGUGCCAAGUACCUAAGGGUUCACUGCCUUGUUUGAGGAAUCGCAGAGCAUCAUUUCUGAUUGGUUCUUAGAGCCUGCAUCUUGUACCACUGGGACUUCUGGAGACCUCUGGGGACCGUUGACUAUGCUGGGAGGGUGCAGAAAUGAAGCUGAUGGCAGAAGCAGGCUCCCAGCUCCUCUUCUUCUGCUCAGCCAGGUGAUUCUUACCUCCAUUGGCCUUUGGAUGUCUGCGUAAUAAUUUGUUGAGAAUCAUUAGAGAACAACUAAUCCAAAAAAUCUAUCAUCCUUUAUUUGUGUUGACUUUCUGAUUAUGCCUUCAUUCACUCUUUUUAUUACUUAUACACAUGUCUGUUUUUAUUCUUCCCUACUCUUUUCUUAAAGUUGGUCAUAUUUCUACACUUGAGAUCUUCCAGUUUCUGUGAAUGUUGAGGGGUUCACAAAGUGGCUUGGCCUCAGACCUCUAUAUCCUUGUUGUUCUGUUUGGACUUAGGACUUUUUUCCUGGCUAUCCUGCCAAUACUUUUCCAUCUAACAGAAACGCAAGCUUCAAGAGCAAGUUAUUUUUAUAACAGAUCAUGUGAGCAAUUCCUCCAUAGCAUUGGUUGUAGAACAGGUCAGUUGGCAUGUGGCCUCCUGAGGGCCUUGCAUGGGGUUCUGGACCCAGCGGGGGCCACAUCUCUGAGAAUUCGUUCCCUGUGGGUGUCUGGGGUGCAUCGUUACUUCUGAGAUGUUAUGACUCAGCAGAUGAGAUUUGUCCGUCUGCUCAGUGAGAGGAAUUCCAAUGCUGGGUCUUGACUCCCGCUGCAGGGAGCUCUCUGGGCCCGGGCAUGUUGGAUGGAGUUGUGAUGGGUGUGCCUCCCUCGGACUUACUCUGGCCAGGAACUGCAUCUGCUCCUCUAAGGAGAUUUGAGCAGGUGAAUGGAGUUUCUGUCAUUCCUGGUCUAGAGUUCAUGUGUGAAGGUCAAAUAUAGGUGGGGACUUGGCAGCACACAACUCUGAGUGAAAGACACGAUCAGCGUGAUAGACAGGUGUCUUGCUAUGUGACUUGCCAUUGCGGUCACUGGUUAUACAAAGUCUCUGUUUAGAAAUAGCAAAGAUCCAAGAAAGCAGAAGAGUGGGGGUGGGAGUGGGGCUAAAUGUGUUGCUCUUCAGUGGAAAUCUGCCCAUUUUGUUGAAAAGAAAGGAAACAGGGUACACAAAUGCUGUUUGGGAACAUUGUGUCAGGAUCACCUAGCUUUGACGAUGAGAGUGUUUUUUAAAACGGAAACCAUGUCAUUUUCCUUCUAGAGAGAAUUUCCUGGUAUGUCAAUGUAGCUUCAGAAAUAGGUCUCAGUGUUCUGGCUCAGGGCGAGGUUACAAAAGAGGCUUCGGUAGCGUCCUCAGGCCCGCGUGCCCUGUGUUCUUAACAGCCUCAUGGGGCCUAGAGGAACUUUUACAUGGUAGACACUGAGUGAAUACACAGAUUCCUAGAUUUGAGAUAUUUUCAAAAUAGGGCUAGCAUGUAUAAAGAAUCAAACUUAGUCAUUCCAUUGAAGUGAAAUUGGAUUAUAAUUUAGAAAUAUUUAUAAGCCAGAAAUGGUUGUGUAAAUGUUAGUUUUCAUAUUUUGGUUUUCUAAGAGUCACAUUUUAUUGCCAUAUAGCACAAAAUUUGACAAUGAGGUAUAGAAAUCCAAAAUUUUCUUGGGUACAAUUGAACAAAUCUUUUAAUCUCUUCAGUUCUAUCUGCCUAAGUGAGGAGAGUAGUUGUGGAGCAUUGUAGAAAGGAUAAAAUGAACAUUAGGAUACUGAGGGUUUGGUCUGAAUUCUGUUUUUUCAUUGCUACUGGAAGUGCUGUCUUUGGUAUCCUCAUGCAUACAAGAAGGAUUUGGAAAAUGUCAGUGAGUUUGAAACUGGCUGUACAGUUGAAUGAGCUGGGCAGUUGAAAGUACCCGUGAUGCUCUGGCCUUACCUUAGAUCAGAGAUUCUUAUAUUUUAUCAAGCAUCAGAAUCACCUGCAGAGCUUGUUGAAUGCAGAUUGUUGGCCACAUCUCCAGAAUUUCUCAUUCAGUAGAUUUGGGAUGGAGCCCAACGAUUUGCAGCUGGUCCAGAGACCACCUUGUGAGAUCUACUACCUGAUUUAAUUGGUUUGAAGGUGAAGGUGGAGUCCAGGCUUUUUAAAACAGUGUCUGUAUUUUCAGAGCAGAUAACCAAUCAAAUUGAGCAGAUGGUCUUUUAAAGUCUAAGCUUCUAUGGUUCUGUGAAAAAAAUUGUUUACAUGGAAUUUAAAUCAUUCAGAAUUUUUAUUGCUUACAUUGAUCAGAUCCAUAAAAUAUCUGUUUAACUAUUACAUUACCCUAGCUACAGAAAUUUGUAAGUUUUCAAAAGCAUGAAGGAGUUUAAUAACUUGUAAGACUUUCAGAGAUUGUUAUAAUUUUUGCCUCAAAAAAAUAAAAUAAAAUAGCUUGGUGGAAAAGAGCACCUAUGCAUUCAAUUUGUUUCCCUCAAAUGCUAAGGGUUAAAAUAGUACUCAAAAUUGUUAGAUGUGAAGUUUUGAACCCAGUGUUUAAACUCAGUGUUUAAAUAUUUGCAUGUCUUUCUAUGUGACUGCUAAUUUUUAACUACAUUAUUAUCUCUAAGAGAUAAAUAAACUUUCCCUGUACUUAAAGUUUUUAAAUUAAGUAUCUUCUGAUAACAUAAGUAGUAUGAGUAAGGAAAAAAAAUCUAUGUGUACUGUAUUUUUAAAUUUUAAUAAGGUUUGAUAUGGUUUGGCUCUGUGUCUCCACCCAAAUCUCACCUUGAAUUGUAAUAAUCCUCACGUGUCAAGGACCAGCAGGUGGAGAUAAUUGAAUUAUGGGGCCGGUUUCUCUCAUACUGUUCUUGCGAUAGUGAGUUCUCAGGAGAUCUGAUGGUUUUAUAAGCAUCUAGCAUUUCCCCUGCUGGUACAUUCUCUCUUCGCCUGCUGCCAUCCAUGUAAGAUGUGACUUGCUCCUCCUUGCUCUCUGCCAUGAUUGUGAGGCUUCCCCACCACUUGGAAAUGUAAGUCAAUUAAACCACUUUCUUUAGUAAAUUGCCCAGUCUCGGGUAUGUCUUUAUCAGCAAUGUGAAAACGGACUAAUACAACGUGAUUGUUUAAAUGCUGAUAUGAAAGCAGUGCUGAAUGUGGAUCUUCUUAUGCCAGAUACUGUUAUAAUUAUUCUCUAGAGAGCUGGCCAUACAAUUUAUCUCAUUAUUUAUAGAUCUAGCAUGAAUGCCAGUAAGCUGACAAAGCCAAAAGCCAAAAACUAAGAGUUUGUAUUAAUCCAGUUAAUGCCAAAUCUAGUCAUCCUCCAUCAUCCUACCUCUGUGUUCUGCAUGAAAUAUAAUUGGCCUUUGUGAUGGAACCAGUUUUCUUGCAUUGAAAAUAAAAUUUGUUCCUCAAAA